AGUCGCAGCGGGGCCAUCUUCGGCGGGCGAGUGGGCUCGGCCUGUGCAACCCGCACCUGCGUCCCUCGCCCGGCCCGAUGGCGCCGCGGCCGCUGGGCCCCUUGGUGCUGGCGCUGGGCGGCGCCGCGGCGGUGCUGGGCUCGGUGCUCUUCAUCCUCUGGAAGACCUACUUCGGCCGCGGCCGAGAGCGGCGCUGGGACCGGGGAGAGGCCUGGUGGGGCGCGGAGGCUGCCCGCCUCCCCGAGUGGGACGAGUGGGACCCCGAGGACGAGGAGGACGAGGAGCCGGCGCUGGAGGAGCUGGAACAGCGCGAGGUGCUGGUGCUGGGGCUGGAUGGCGCAGGCAAGAGCACGUUCCUGCGCGUGUUGUCGGGGAAGCCACCGCUGGAAGGCCACAUCCCCACCUGGGGCUUCAACUCCGUGCGUCUGCCCACCAAGGACUUUGAGGUGGACCUGCUAGAAAUUGGGGGCAGCCAGAACCUGCGCUUCUACUGGAAGGAGUUUGUGAGCGAGGUGGAUGUGCUGGUGUUUGUGGUGGACUCGGCUGACCGACUGCGGCUGCCCUGGGCCCGACAGGAGCUGCACAAGCUGCUGGACAAGGACCCUGACCUGCCUGUCGUCGUGGUGGCCAACAAGCAGGACCUGAGCGAGGCCAUGAGUAUGGGGGAGCUGCAGCGGGAGCUGGGUCUACAGGCUAUCGAUAACCAGCGGGAGGUUUUCCUCUUGGCAGCCAGCAUUGCCCCUGCAGGACCCACCUUUGAAGAGCCUGGCACCGUGCACAUCUGGAAACUGCUCUUGGAGCUCCUCUCCUAGGCUGGAGCUCUCCUGCUUGCCACCUGCCUGUCAAGACCAUAGUUGUACUGCUGCUGCUUCAUUGCCAGACUGGGCCUGGGGCAAGAGCCACAUGGCAGCAUUUCCCUUUUCCCCUCCUUUGCCUUUCAAGAGCAGGGCCUGGGCAAGGCCAAGAACCAUGCAGAAGCCUUCCUGGUGAGGUGGCCGUGAAGCCGAAGCAGGGAGGUGGGUGAGACAGAGGGUGGGGAGGAUAGUGUCUGGCUCAUUCCAGGCUGGAAUGUGGAUCCAGCUUUCCCUUCUCUUACCUGUACAGUGAGAUGCUCAGUGGGCUCAAUCCUCCACUACAGGUCCCGGUACCUGAGGAACCAGUGUAGGUGUCAGAAAUACUCCUAGAGCCUCAAGGUCUCCCAGUCCAGAAACAGUCUGGUGACGUCAUGCCCUUCUCAUGUGGGCAGCUUCUGAGUGGUGACACAGCAAGCCUUUGUUCCUGUCCUGCAUUGUCCAGCCCCAGCUCCACCUAAGUGACUUGUGGCCUUGUGCAAUCUCUGCCUCUCUGACCCCAGGGCCAUUAUUUUUAAAGGGAGGUGGUUUCCUAAUUCGGAGAUGCCUUUCCCAGCCAUGGGAGUGUGAAGUGCUAGGAUGAACCUGGCCAUCCUAGCAAGGAGCUUUCUGAAGACCUCCCUGCCUUUCCCUGAGCCCAGGCCUGGCCUGCCAGCCUCUCUUGACUACAGAAUAACUGAUAUUCACCCACCAAACAGAAAAAGUGAAGGCUGGGUUUUUCCCCUCUAAUCUGGAGACAAGCUGCUGCUCUCGUACUAACUGUGCCAGUGCCCAUGUUUACAGAAGUCAGGGGAAGGAAGGAGCCUGUGUCCCUGGGACGACAGUCAACUGGAGCUAGGUGUUGACCUCAGAACUGCAUUUUAUUUAUUAAUUUAUAAGCAGAACAGGCCAGAGUUCUAGGCUCUGUUUCUAGGUGCUGUUUUCAAAACCCCAGAUGACAGUCAUAGAAAAUUUGGAACUUAGGAAAAUAGCUGGAAUCAUGAAUGACAAUGAGAUAACAUACAGAUGUCAGUGGAGACAAAGUUGUGGGUUCCUCCUCCCACCUGGCUUUGAGGCUGUCGUCGAUAUCAUAGUACUUUACAUGGAUUCACAUGAACUGAAACGCCACCACUUGGCCCAGGAUGUUGAAAGGGUGCAAAUUCCUUCUGGGUAGAUAAGAAAUGACUCUGGGAGAGGAUUUCCCUUAUGUGAAUCUAGGUAAAAAGAUGGAAAAAAAUUGUAUUAUGUGAUCCUAAGGACAGGAAUAGCAGACCAGCCAACGGGAUGGCCUUGGGUACAUCACUCAGCCUUUCUGGACCCAAUUUUUCCCCAGUGAAAGCCAAGUUGGACUGAAUUUCUGGAGUUCUCAUCAGUGCACAUUCCAUAGUUCUCCAGUGCUUGGCGAUCAGCCCAAUUGAAGGACUGGCUCUGUACUGACACUUAUUAUCGGUACAGGCAAAGAGGAGCCUGUUGUCUGUUAGGGACCACUAAAUCAACAACCACAAAUGGAUUUUUUUUUUAAGAGGAGCUGUGCACCUCAAUUUGCUGUCUAGUUGAGAAUAGAGAUUGUGUGCCUUCAUUUCAUUUGACAUUUACCCAGCAUGCCUCAGUUCCACACCGUGACCAGUGUAAGAAGAGGAACUAUGAUAAAAACAGUUCAACAAGCCGCAAGGAGGGUGGGAAAUUCUGAAGUCCAGAAGCGAGUGUGAUCUUUGGAAUAGUGGCUGCUGUGCCCUUGGGCGCCAUUUGAAGAAUCACUGUUCUUGAAAGUGCUGGUUCACUUUCUGCAGUAAGAAGUGAUUUAUGGGCUUUUAUGUAAAAUUUUAAGAAUGACUUGGGUUUCAGAGUAGCCUUUGAAACUUUGCUGGCAGCUUUUCAUUUUGUCAUUGGAAGGCUAAGAGACUUUUCUCCUUUGUUCUAUGAACUCCUUGUUCUUCAGGGCUUGAAGGCAAAAAAACCUUAGACAACUUUAACGAAGUUUAAAAAGUAUGUUCUGUUUUUGAGCAGAAAAAAGAUUCGUGAACUGGUUAGUACUUAGCACCAAAAGCAGUUCAGAAUGCUCAGCCCCACAAUGUGUGUAGGCUACAUUUAUAGCCAGAGAAACGAAAAUAACUUAGGUUGCCUGAUUGGCUGCAGUCUGGCAUUUGCCUUACCUGAACAUGUUUUAGCAGCCUUCAGCCGACGAUUGACUGAAGGUUUGGCUGCUGUGAUUGGCUAAAAUUCGGCUACUUGUUAGAAGAACAUACUUUUAGGUUAGGUUACGAGUUGUUUACACGUUAAGUUACAAUUCACUGUGUACAGAGGCAGCUUUAGGCCAGACUUAAUUCAGCUUCACAGUGUCCCUCAUUUUGCUCAGCCCCUUAAUUUUGAGAGAUUGACCAAAAUCCCACGCACUGACACUACCUUCUGUCACUAUUUGACCUCAUUAUGGAACUCACAGUUUACAAUGUUAAAUCAGUUAGCGGAUUCUGUAUGUCUUCAUGUUUCUGUUACUCUAACCGUAAUGAGACCAUUUGAGGUACAAAGGAUGACUGCAUUGGUGUACUUAAGACUACAACACAUCAGUGGGGACCUUAGGAUGGCUAUCAGGAGUGUAAUACCAAGAAACUGGAAUGCAUCCCUUAAUAUGAGUCUCCACAAACCAAACUGAUUGGAAUCAAACAACUCAAGUUCAGACGAUAAAAAUAGUUCAACAGCGUGCAAGCUCUGCUGCUCAUAGCCUGUUCAGGGUAUAAUGGCAAUUAAGGACAUAGUUCACUAUGAAGUACCUUAAUUGUAAAGUGUUUGAUUUUUUAGUUAGCUUUUGGUAACACAAGUCAUGGUGAUUGGGAUACCCACUAAAAGAAACAUGAAGAUUAGAAAACCUUGAACAGCUAAGCUUGCUGUCUACCAUUCAGGAUGCCUGCAAACCAACCACUAGCUGCUCCUGCAAACACAUUAUGUGUUCCUUUUCCCUGAGAAAUAUCCUUGAUGUGUUUGGUGGCAGUAUCUACAGAAGCGGCAGCCACCACCGCCUUUUGAAGCUCUCCAUAGUAGUAGAAUCAGGAAAGAUAAGCACAGCGUUCAGUUUUGUUCAGCACCAUACACAAGCUCCUAGCUGGGCAAAGGAAAUCUAAAGCUGCAUGAAGUUCCAUUACGUGUUUUUGUUGAACACAGGUGGCCUCAUCCAUCCAUCCAUCCAUCCAUCCAUCCAUCCCUCCAUCCGUCCACCCGUCCACCCGUCCACCCAUCCACCCACCCACCCAUCCAUCCACCCACCCACCCACCCAUCCACCCAUCCAUCCAUCCAUCCACUCAUCCACCCAUCCACCCAUCCAUCCAUCCAUCCAUCCAUCCUUCCAUCCAUCCACCCAUCCACCCAUCCAUCCAUCCACCCAUCCAUCCAUCCAUCCAUCCAUCCAUCCAUCCAUCCAUCCAUCCAUCAUCCACCCAUCCAUCCAUCCAUCCAUCCAUCUGUGGCUUCUACCUGUGCGAAUCUCUGUGCUACAAAAUUCUUUUCAAUUUAGCAUUAACUUUAAUUUCCAUACAGUUGGCACCUCACUGCCGCCAAAAGUGAGUCCGCAGGAACUCCACUGGAAUAUUUGCUCAGGGGAAACUAACUAAUCAUCUGUUUCAAGGUUGGUAUUCAUUUUAGUCUUUGACCUCUGAUUAUGGGGACUUUCAGGGAAAGCUGUUUGCAAGGUGAGCAUGAAUCAGGUGAAACAGCAAGAUCUGAAGUCAGGACAGAGUAAGCAAAUUAUCCACAGACCUAAUAUGUACCCUCUGAAGCUGGAAAGUGGGGGCCACCUGGUAGCAUUUGAGCAGGGGUCACUUAUGUUCCCCCAUAAGUCUGCACAGCUCCUAAACAAGGUCCAGUGGGCAACUUAUUUUUAUGUGGUCCCUUUAUAGCAUGCUGUAAGGGUGCAUAACCACAGCCAGUGAGAAGGAACCCUACUGGAUUUAACCCAGUGACAUUAUAUAAGCAAUCGCUUGGAGCCACAUAGGUAGUUCCCAGGUCCUGAAUAUGUGGUGCCUGAAAGCAUAGGUGUAGGCAGUGUUCCUUGCAUAGGCAUUACCUGGACAGGUUUUUUUCCAUAUUGGCACUUAUUAAUUGAAAAGGUCAGGGUACCACUUCCAAUGAGUGUAGGGAAGCAAGCAGUAGUGGUGUUUAGAAUAUCAAGGUUAGCUGCUGGAUGCGGUGGCUCACGCCUGUAAUCCCAGCACUCUGGGAGGCUGAGGUGGACGGAUCACGAGGUCAGGAGAUCGAGACAAUCCUGGCUAACACAGUGAAACCCUGUCUCUACUAUAAAAUACAAAAAAUCAGCUGGGUGUGACGGCAUGCGCCUGUAGUCCCACCUACUAGGGAGGCUGAGGCAUGAGAAUCACUUAAACUUGGGAGGCAGAGGUUGCAGUGAGCUGAGAUCACGUCACUGCACUCUAGCCUGGGAGACAGAGCGAGACUCCGUCUCAAAAAAAAAAAAAAAAAAAGGUUAGCAUUCCACUCUUCCUUUGGGGUUUCAGGGUGACUUAUUGGGAAAAUGGAGAGAUACUGGCAUUAAUGGAAUCGUUUCCUGAUUUGAGCGUUAAGUCACAAACCCAACAGGAACUCCAGUUUCUUGCUAGAGCAUUAGCCUUUGCUAAAGCCGGCCCCAGAUUAUGGUCCCACGGAUUUUCCCAUAAAGAAAGGGAAAGGAUUUGCGGACAGAAAAUAGGAAAGAGAGGGAGAAAGAUAAGAUUUUUGCGAUUGCAGUGAAGUCUUCAUCCACAUCUAGGGAAAGCUGUUCAUGUCUAGGACGUGAUCUGCUUCUGGGGAAAAACUUCCCUGGUUAGCUUUACCUUAAAGUCUCCAACAGGUGUGUAGUUCCAGGAGUCUGGAGAGGUCCUUUUGAGUUGUGAGAUGUGGACCCAAGGUUCGAAGCCCUGAAGUUUUACCACAGUGUGGGUAAUAGAAGAACUUGGUAUUGUCUCUUUCUGUGAGGUUUAAGGGCACUUUUUCUCUGAUACCAUCUCCAGAAGACCUAGUCUCAGGUUACAGAUUGUGAAGGCUUUGAUGGUCCUCUGUGGGUCACAGAAAGUUUAUUUUAUUUUGUCAAAAUACAGUGUGACAUAAUGCAUUACAGCUUUGUAGUAUUUAGUGGCAUCAGCAUUUAGGAGAGUAGGAACUACGUGAAGUUCUGUUAGGAGCACAGGCUUUCUAGUAACUAUUUCAUAGGGGUCAAUCUGUGUCUGUCGUAGGAAUGGAUCUGAUCUGCUGACCAAAGGCAAUGGUUGGCUUUCUUCUUCAGAGAUCAGAAAAAAAUGAAAUUCAAAGCCAAUGGUGGUAUCUUUGGCCAAGAUAAUCCAAUCGAUUCAGUUAAUUUUGCCAAUUUUAGUUUUAAAAUAUUUGUCCUUUUGACCUUUCCAGAAGACUGAGGGUGAAAGGGACAAUGGUAGUACCACUGUGUUUCUAACACUUUAUUUAGCUGCUUCAUAGUUUGUCCAAUAAAAUGAGUUCCUCUGUCACUGGAGAUUUUUCCAGAGAUGCCCCAUAAAGGAAACACAUGUUCUUAUAACUCCUUAGCUACUGCCAUAGCAUCAGCUCUCCUACACAGGAAAGCUUCUAUCCAACCAGAAAACAUGCCAACUAUUACAAGAACAUACUGAUACUUAAUUGAGGGUGGCAGUUGAAUGAAGUCCAUCUGUAAGCGUUCAAAUGGUCCAUCAGGUGUUGGUGGAAAUACACCACUUGGAGUUUUUAUUAUCUUCCCUGGAUUAUGGGUUUGACAAACCAGAUAUUGGUUAUAACCCAUUUCAGCAUUUUACAGUGGUCACACUAUCAGUAUUUUUUAUAAUCUGGAUCAUCUUGCUCAUUUGUGAGGUGCAGAGGUUGUUUUUUGUUUUUUUGUUUUGAGACAGGAUCUCACUCUGUCACCCAGGCUGGAAUGCAGUGGUGCAAUCAUGGCUCACUACAACCUCCACCUCCAGAGAUCAAGCAGUCCUCCCACCUCAGUCUCCUGAGUAGCUGGGACUACCAGUGUGCGCCACCAUCCCCAGCUAAUUUUUUGUAAUUUUUAUAGAGAGGGUUUUAUCCUCUUGCCCAGGCUGGUCUUGAACUCCUGGGCUCAAGCUGUCAGUCCAGCUCAGCUUCCCAAAGUGCUGGGGUUAUAGGGAAGAGCCACCGUGCCUGGCCAAGUGCAAAGCUUUUAACAAUAGAAGUUUCAAGGGCUCAGGAAGGACCAGGGGGCCAUCUAGGCUCUCCAUGAGUUCACGCUUAACAUUAUGUUUACGUCUGUCAGAUAACAAUUUUGGUUUUCCACAUCAGGUGCAUUGCACUGUUAGAUGGGUCAUCAUAAAGGUCAUCAAUCUAGUGGCAUUCAUUCAAUUUGCACAUCCUAACUGUUUCAGCACUAUCUGAUUUAGCAUGAAAAUCUGCCAGGGCAGUCCCUUGAUAUUCAGGUUCAGCUUUCCAUGUAUGGGCUUCAAUCUUAUAAGAAUUUGUUAUUUAUUUUUCACCUUUACUCAAGAUAGCUUGGAACUUAUACCAAUUUGUGAUGGCAACAGGAUAGUAGCAAGUUCAUCCACUUGAGUCUGUUUUUAAUAGGGGCUCCACUAGAAGUGAGAAACCCUCUUUGUUUCCAUAACAUGCCAAAAUUGUGGACUGCAAAGGCAUGUAUAUAUACAUAGCAUGUCUGCUAUGUAUAUAGCAUUUUCUGAUUUCCCUUUAGCUAUAUGAUAAGCUCAAGUGAGAGCAAAAGUUCUGCAGUUUGAGCUGACUGAAACUGGGAAGAGUCCGCUUUUUAUUAACUCAUUUUGGGUUUUAAUGACAUAUUUUGCCAAAGAAUAAUUUCAAAUGGGGGCCGGGCGCUGUGGCUCACGCCGGGCGUGGUGGCAGGCACCUGUAGUCCCAGCUACUUGGGAGGCUGAGGCAGGAGAAUGGCGUGAACCCAGGAGGCAGAGCUUGCAGUGAGCCGAGAUCGCGCCACUGCACUCCAGCCUGGGCAACAGAGCGAGACUCUGUCUCAAAAAAAAAAAAAAAAAAAAUUUCAAAUGAUGUUGGUCUACUUGCUGAAAAAUGCUGGGUUUGACUGGAAUUUAAUAGACUUUCCACAGCACGUGGAACUUGCAAAAAAAAAAGUUCACUCCCUAAAACCAGAUCAGAUGAACCCUUUACCAAUCUGGGGGUUGCUGCCACUGCCUUUAAACAAUUGGGAUAUGCCUUAGCUAUGGGGUCUAAUUGCAGGCCAUGAUAUGUGAUGGGCCUGUGCUUUCCCAACUAUGUUCUUUUUUAUGUAUGUAUGUAUGUAUUUAUUUUUUGAGAUGGAGUUUUGCUCUUCUUGCCCAAGCUGGAGUGCAGUGGUGUAAUCUCAGCUCGCUGCAAUCUCCGCCUCCCAGGUUCAAGUGAUUCUCCUGCAUAAGCCUCCCGAGUAGCUGGGAUUACAGGUGCCCGCCACCACGCCCAGCUUAUUUUUUGUAUUUAGUAGAGAUGGGGUUUCACCGUGUUCGUCAGGGCUGGUCUCGAUCUCCUGACCUCAGGUGAUCCACCCGCCUCGGCCUCCCAAAGUGCUGGGUCAACUAUGUUCUUGAGUAAGAACUCCUGAUGCCUGAUUGUUAUGUUUAUGAACAAACAAGGUGAAGGGUUCAGUAUAAGUUGGAAAUCCUAGAGCAACCAUAUCUGUUACUUUCCAUCCUGGUUAUAUUUCUUAAUUAGACUGCGAAGUUCUGAAUGAAGUCCUUUUUAAAUAGAGCAGUUAAUGCCAUUUCUGUCUCUGCAGGUUUCACAAGUAGUGUUUCUAAAUGAGCUCUAUAAUCUGAAACCGGUUCAUCUUUCUUUUGCCCACAAGAUUAUGUGAUUGACCAAUCAAUUUUUUGUGGAAAAGCCCUAGGGAUUGAAUUUAAAAGAUCUUCAGCAAUUCUUCCAGUUCCUUUUUGCCUCCUCUUGGGGUUUUGGAGUGGUCUUUAGUAUCCUCAGGCUGUUGCCAUUCUGCUCCUGCUGUCAAUUUUCAAGCUUCACCAGUAUCAUGUGAAUAAAUUGGUAAAGAUUAGAGAGUCCUGAAUCAUAAGCUCUUAUGAGGAUUCUCAAUUUUCCAGUACGUUUUUGAGUAUUUUCUCUUGGAUUAGUUAAGUCUUUAUGAUGGCUCUAAGCUCAGCUUUAGACCAUGGAGUAAAAGUGGUUACAGCAGGCAGGCUGGUUGACUAGAGAGUCUCACUUUGUAAGGCAUUUGUCCAACUUCCCCUUUUUCAUUAGCCUCAAGGAGAAAAGGUAACUGAGCAAAAGGGUUACUGUACUCAAAGCAUCGAGGCAAAGAAGAGACAGAGAAGGAGCAAUCCAGGUUCAUGUGCUGCAUGAGCCUUUCAUUUGCGUUUUGUAAAGAAUCUUUUAGGCAAUUUUAGAUUUGUAUAAUCCUUUAGAUGCCUCUGCAUACCGAUUUAAAAUGCAUCCCGUUGUUUUUGUGGCGUUUUCGAUCCUUUCUUUUCUAAUGUGUCCCAUAAAUAAACAGUUUUAUUUAAAGUUUCCUCAUCGUGGCCAUUUUAAUUCUAAGUUGUUCCUAGUAAGGUUAACCUGUUUUUCUAAAAACAAGUUCUGGGUCCAUAAUUUUGGUUUUUUUUUUUUUUUUUUUUUGAGACAGAGUCUUACUCUGUCACCACCCAGGCUGUAGCGCAAUGGCACGAUCUCAGCUCACUGCAACCUCCGCCUCCCAGGUUCAAGCAAUUCUCCUGCCUCAGCCUCUCAGCCUCCCGAGUAGCUGCGAUCGAUCACAGGUGUGCACCACCGCCCAGCUAAUUUUUGUAUUUUUAGUAGGGAGGGGUUUCGCCACAUUGGCCAGGCAGGUGAGGUGAUUUGCCCGCCUCGGCCUCCCAAAGUGUUGGGAUUACAGGUGUGAGCCAUCACACCCGGACUUGUUUUGUUUUUUGAGAUAGAGUGUUGUUUUGUCGCCCAGGCUGGAGUGCAGUGGCGUGAUCUCGGCUUACUGCAACCUCUGCCUCCAGGGCACAAGAGAUUUUGCCACCUCAGCCUCCUGAGUAGCUGGGACUACAGGCAUACACCACCACACGCCCAACUAACUUCUGUAUUUUUUGUAGAGAUGGGGUUUUGCCAUGUUGCCCAGGCUGGUCUCAAACUUGUGAGCUCAAGAGAUCUUCCUGCCUCAGCCUCCCAAAGUGCUGGGAUUACAGGCAUCAGCCACCACACCCAGCCCCAUAAUUCUUACAUAUAAAAUUAGAUGGAGUCCCAGACUCCUUGGAUUGAAACAAACCCGUUAUCAAAAGGAUAACCUACCCAAUGCCUCUAACUGGAUCCAUCCAGUUUAUUAUGGGAUGCAGUCCAAUCCAGGACCCAGUCCAGUAAAAAUUGCUCAGAUAAACUUGGAGAGCUCAAAACACAAAUUUAUGGAGCUCAGAAUCCUAGGAAGAACUCACUAUGACCUCCAGUUGCUGUGAGGGGUCAGUGGGCACAAUGGGCCCUGGCAGAUACCUUUUUUGCAUGGUCACUCAGUGCUCCUGGAGGUUGCUGAAGUUAUACUUUGGAUCCUACUUCUGACACCAGUUUGUUAAAAGAAAAAUUUUAUAGACAAGUUAACUUUAACAGAGCAGAAAAGGGUUCAUGAACCAGGUAGUGCUCAGGACCAAAAGCGAUGGUUCAGAAUGUGUGCAGGCUAUAUUUAUAAGCAAAGAAACGGAAUUGGCAUACAGAGAUAGCCUGACUGGCUGCAGUCUGGCGUCUGCCUUCUUUGGACAUGUUUUGGCAGCCUUCAGCCUAUGGUUGGCUGAGAUCUGACUACUUGUUACAAGAGUAGACUCUUACAUCAGGUUGCAGGGUGUUUACACAUUAAGUUAGGUUAUAAUUCACUAUGUACAGAGGCAGCUUUAGGCCAAACUUAACAAAGGUCACCUUUGGAACCAGCACUAAUUGUUGAGGGGGUCCCUGGGGUCCCUUUUUACCUAAUGAAGAUCUGUCUGAGUCUAAUGAAUAUAUUGUACAAUUUUUAAAGUCCCCAGUUGUGGGAGGUGAACUUGAAGAAUAAAGUUUCAUUAUGUUUA